CAUGUUGUCUUGAGUAGAUCACUUCUAUUUUUCCUUCAAAGGCUGAAAAUAACUGCCUAACAUACUAUGUUUAGUAGGUCCUAAAUACUUUUUGUUGUUUAAUGAAUUUACAGGUAAUAAAGAGAAAGCACAGUGUUUCUUGAAUGGAUGUCAGGGAAUUUCUAAUUUUUUUCUUUUUUGAUAGAAAAAAGUAAUCAAAACAUAAACAUCUGAUUGGAGUCUUUCAGUUAGCUUACCUACCUUCAGAAAUAAGCCUAGAGAAAGAGAGCUUCAUCUGGUAGUUUAACAGAAAUGAAUUGUAAAUGACUCUUAAGAAGAAUUGACAAUUUUUCGGAAUGUUGUACUAGAUGUUUUAGAUUCUUUUUGCCACAUAAACUCCACUUCAGAGAAAUGGGGUUCUACAUAGUACUCUUGUAUCGCCCCUGUAAUACCUUUACACCUCAAAAUACCAGUUGCAGAAAAAUAGAAUGUGUUGCUGAUGCCUAUAAAUGGGAAAAUCCUGACAUCUGUCUUCAUCCUCCAGUUAAUCUUCAUGUAGUUUUUAAAAAAAUUAAUUCAACACACAUGUAAUUUACUUCCUUUUCAGAAAAUUUGUUGCUAAUUUUUAUUUUAUAAUGAGCCUCUUGGGAUGUUGCUAAUUCUAAAAAUAUGUAAUACCCGCGGUUUCCCACCAUCUUCUGCAGUUUCUUUUUCUAUUAUUUUUUUGGCUACAGUUUUCUUUUUCCCCUAAGCUGUCUAAAAUAAGCUAAGAAAUGUUUAAAUGUAGUUGACAAGAAACACAGUCAGUAAUUUAUCAUGCUAAAAUUUCAACAUACAAGGUGCAAUGAAAUCUGUUUUAGGGAUAGUACACUUUUGAAGGGGGCUAAAGCAGGGACAGCAAAUAAAUUUCGUUUGGGGUACCAAAUCUGAUUGUUUAGUGGUGGCUGCCUAGAGUGCUGUGUUUAGAAAACUGGGAGUCCUUGUUCAAACUUAGCAGGAAAGAGUACUGUGAUUAGCAAUUUCUGCUGUUGGUGAGCGGUGGACUUUUGGCAUGGAUGCCAAAUACAUUCAGUGUUUAUUGAUGCCGUUUACAUGUCACAGGUCUAGAUGCUGAUACCUCAUAGACUAAAAUCUCUGCUUUCAUGGUGUUUACAUUCUAGUAAUAAGACACAAACCAUAAAAUAAAUAAAAUACAUUGCGUUUUAAGAAAAAUGGCUGGGCGCAGUUGCUGACACCUGUAAUCCUAGCACCUUGAGAGGCUGAGGUGGGAAGAUCCCUCUUGUCCAGGAGUUCAAGACCAGCCUGGGCAACGUGGUGAGACCUUGUCUCUACAAAGAAGUUUCUUAAAAAAUUAACUGGACGUGGUCCCAACUACUCGGGAAGCUGAGGUGGGAAGAUCACUUAAGCCUGGGAGAUUGAGGCUGCAGUGAACCAUGAUUGCACCACUGCACUCCAGCCUGGGCAACAGAGCGAGACCCUGCCUCAAAACAAUAGAAGUUAAAAAAUAAAUAAAAGAAAAAUGACCUGAUUUAUUCAAAAAAUUAAUAGCAAGAAAUAGGGAGGGAGAACUAUAAGAUUAAAAGAGACUUAAGAGGCUUUUCCACCAAAUGCAAUGUAUGAAGCUUAGUUCUAUCCUGCUUUGAGCAAACUAACUGUAAAAAGACAUUUAUUCAAAAUUGGGGAAAUUUAGACUCUGGAUAUUUAAUGAAAAGGAUUUGUCCAUUUUUUCAGGUGUGAGAAUGUACUUUUUAAGUGUUCUUUUAGAGAUGUAUAAUGAAGUGUUUACAACUUAAAAUGUGAUGUGUGGGUUUUUACUUCAAAAUAUUGAAAGGGAGAGGAACAUAGAUGAAACAAGAUUGGCCAUAUAUUGAAAAUUGCUGAAGGUAGAUGCUAUAUGGAUACAUGAGGUUUCUUACUUCCUCUUUAUUUUUGUGUAUGUUUGAAAUUUCCCCUAAUAAACAGUUUUACACACAAACAGGAAAAUAAAGCAGGGAAGGGGAAGGGAGAAUAAAUGGGAUAUGUGUAUGAGGUUCGGAGGAGGAUGCAGUUUUUUGCUUUUUGUUUCUUGUUUUUUGUUUUUGAGAUGGAGUUCUGCUCUCAUCACCCAGGCUGGAGUGCAGUGGGGCGAUCUCAGGUCACUGCAAAUUCUGUUUCCUGGGUUCAAGUGGUUCUCCUACCUCAGCCUCCUGAGUAGCUGGGAUUACAGGCACACGCCACCACGCCCAGUAGAGUUUUGUAUUUUUAGUAGAGACAGGGUUUCACCAUGUUGGCCGGACCGGUCUGAAACUCCUGACCUCAGGUGAUCACCUACCUCCGCCUCCCAAAGUGCUGGGAUUACAGGUGGGAGCCACCACACCUGGCCAAGAUGCAGUUUUAAAGGGUAGUGAGAAAAGACUUCAUUGAGAAGAUGAUAAAUAGUUAAAGUGAGUAAUGACCUGAAGGAGGUAGCACAGCAAGCCUUGCAGGUCUCCUUGGAGCAAGACAUUAUACACAGAGGGAAUAGUAAGUGCAGUGGCCCUGAGAUGGGAGCGUGCCUACAACUGCAAGAAACUACAAGAAGACAAGGGUGUGAGCCAGGCAUAGUGGCUUGCACCUGUAGUGCCAGCUACUCAAGAAGCUGAGGUGGGAGGAUCAUUUGAGCCCAGGAGUUCCAGACCAGUCUGAGCAGCAUAACCAGAUCCUGUCUAAAAAAAACAAAACAAAACAAAAAAAACUAGCGUAACUAGAUCAGGGUGAGCGUGAGUACAUAAAAUCAGCAUCAGCAUGGGAAAGGAAGGUUAGAGAAGACUAAAUUGUGUAGGGCUGGUUAUCCAUCUUUAAAGGAAAAAUAUUUUAUACACUUAUCUAAAAUAAGUCUUAUACUUUAGAGUAGUCACCAUGGAAGCUAUACACUUAACAAUACUAGCAUUACUCAAUAUUUUUAGAAAAAAAAAUUUUUUUUGUCGUCUAAGCCAGUUUAAGAGCCACACGUGAAAAUAGCUCAUUACUUUGUAUUUGCUCCUUGUUUUUAAGGAAAAAAGGGGUGAUUGGCCACGUGAUAUUUCAUGUUAUUUAUCAGAUAUGACUCACAGAGGAUCUUGACAGAAAGAAAAUGGGAAGUAACUUGAGGCUAUUUCUAAAAAUCAGAUCCAGUCUGAGAAGGCAGUUAUUGUUUGUAAAAGUCAGAUCCACCCAUAGACUAAAAAGGAAUUUUAAUAAUGUUGUGGAUAAUUGUAGCAUCAUUUGGAAUAAGGGUAUAUAACCUCUGAGAGUGACUAGUAUGGAAGGCACCAUACUAAUUUGGAUAUUUUAAGGUCUCACAAAAUGCGCACACACACACACACAUACAAGAUCAUAUACAAUUCUUAAUACUAAGUAUCAAAACAGUAAUUUCAGGUAAAUUUCAUUUAUAUUCUGCAUUCAAGACUAAAGGGAUGGUAUUUAAAACACAGUGAAAUUGUUUAAGUCUUGUCGCUAUGGCAUACACUUGGGGAAGGAACUAAAAGACUAACACAUGUUAGUGUUAAGAGAUGAAUCUGGUUCUUAAGUCUUCUUAUAUUCAUGCUUCAUUUCUCAGAUUAGUAGUUGUUUUGAGAACAUUCUGAUUUACCAUAAGAACUGUUUUUAUUAAAAAAGGCAUAGGAAAAAUUGGAUCUCAUCUAAAUGUUUAAAUGCCCCCAAAAACCUCAAUAAAUAUGGAUUGUAAAAAUCUACUCUCAGGACAAUAUACAUGUAGGAUUACUAAUUUUGAACAAUUACUAUACUAGUUCAUUCUUUAGAGGUACAGUUUUUCCAACCUGAGAAACUAAACAUUUCAGUGAUUUUUACUCUCCUGAUAAUAUUGAGUAAAGAAAGCCAUUCUUUUUCUUGUUAUUUAUGUCCAAUGGUGGGGGAGCACAACGUUUUCAUUUGUUUUGUUUUGUUUUUGAGACAGAGCCUUGCUCUGUCACCAGGUUGGAGUGCAGUGGCACAAUCUCGGCUCACUGCAACCUCCACCUCCUGAGUUCAAGUGAUUCCCCUGCCUCAGCCUCCCAAGUAGCUGGGAUUAUAGGCGCACACCACUACGCCCAGCUAAAUGUUUGUAUUUUAGUAGAGACAGGGUUUCACCAUGUUGGCAAGGAUGGGCUUGAUCUCCUGACCUCGUGAUCCACUGCCUCAGCCUCCCAGAGUGCUGGAAUUACAGGCGUGAGCCGCCGCGCCCAGCCUCAUUUGUAUUUUUAACCAAUCAUUUAAAAUGUAAUGCCAUGAAGUAGAACUUAUGAACUUUUAUUAUGUAGUUAAUUACAUAGUGACCACUAAGAAUAUAAGUAUAUAACUGUGUAAGGAAUACUUUAACAAAGCUUCCUAUUUUAAACAUUUUUCAGUAAAUUGUUAGGAAUCUAGUUCUUUAAUUCACUCAGAGUUUUUGUCCCUUUAGUGUGUGUAGAUGUAUGUAUGCAUGUGUAUGUAUAGAUAGCCAGACUCUCUUACCAUAUACUGCACAUACUAUCAGGGCUGAGCUGCUAGACUAGAUUAUUUAACGUAUUUUAAACACUAGUUUGUUAACAUGGAACAACUGAGCCCAUAUUUAAUUCCUGGGCUUUCCAUUAACUCUGAAAGUCUUUUAAAACCUUUGAUUCAUCUAAAAAAAAAAAGUGGCAGUGGUUUUUCAUAAAGAUCUUUGAACUUCUAUGAUGAUGACCAUACUGAAGUGUAACUUAUUUUAGAAAGCUUUCAUUCAGGCUGUUGAUUUGCUGGUAAGAUCAUGAAUCUGUUUUUCAUUUCCAUUUUUGUGGAAUAAAUGAAUAACUUCUGACGGAAGAGAAAGAGAGGGAAGGCAGCAAGAGAAGGAAGGAAAGGAAGAAAUUGGAUCUCACAAAAUAGUAAAUAUAAGUAUGGAUAAUUCUCUGAACUUGGAUGUGCUUAAGUGUCUAUGACCUAAUGAGCUAAGGCUCAGAUGUGUAAAUUAAGUAGAGAAUAGAAGUAAUAAUACACCUUGCAUUUGAAGAGAAGUUAUUGCUUUGCAAAAGUGCAUCUUACAUUUCAUGUUGACUUAAACCUUAUGACCAUGAUAAAAUCUAUACUUAAUUUUGGAAAUAAUAAUGAGUAACAAUAAUUGAGAGAUUAUUUGAAAAUUCAAUCUAUUAAGCUUUGUAGAUUUUUACAGCAACAGGUUCAAGGUUAUUCUUCUCAGCUUGUGCAUUGCAAGAUACUUGUAAUUUCCUGCCUGUCUCACUUUCAUCUAUUCAUUACUCUGCCAAUAGCUCUCUUUAUCAUCCUUUGCCAGCUUUAGUCAUGCCUAUUGCUCUUCAACAGCGUUUUCUAUGUUUGUCUGCCAUUUUUAUACUUAUAAAGUAGACUUGGAAUGAAUUAAGGUUAUAAAGUAGUAACCUGUGGAUGGCAAGUACAAUACUUUUCCUAUUUGUGCCAUACUUAAUCUUUUUAAACUUUCCUUGCCUAUUUCUGGUGUGUGCCUUGGUGGAGAUCUCUCAUCAGACACUAAGAGAUAACUACAUGACCUGUAGGAUGCAAUACUUUUUUAACUCAAUAAUGUAGGAAACAGUAGGAAACAGUUUGAGUUUAAACUCAAACUCAUUGAGUUAAUCCUGCAUCCAUCCAGAACCUACAUACCUAAACUAGCAAAGUUUGAUAGUAAAAUUAACAGCCUAGUGGAAUUUCAAAAACUAUUUUCAGCUCUUGAUGUUUGUUGUCUUUUCUAAAAAUGUCAAACAAUUGGGGACCUCAUCAUUACUGUAAUACUAACCAUAUAUGACCUUAGGGGAAAACUGUACUUCUGUUGAGCAUCUCUUUGACAGUCAAGAGGAAAAGAUAAAAAGAUAAGUAAUGUGGUAAAGAAGGUUAUAACUUCUUCCUUCCACAAGAAUGAAUUAUGAAGUGACUGGCCCUGAUAUUUUUCUAGUAACUCAUUGUAGUGCUCAACAUAUCAUUUGGCUUAAUCUUUAGAAGGCACAGUUUAAUUUUAUUUUUUAACAAUAAGUGAAAACAAUUGAAAGUGCUUUGUUGGUUUUUCAAAACUUUAAUGUUGAAUUCCUGGUUCUUGGCAGAUACUAUCCGUAGUAUUUCAUGUUCCUCUGGGUUUAUUUCAGAUUUAAUGAACUGCAUGUACUGGAAGCACUAAAAGCUGAUUGGCUUUAAUUUAGACUACAGUUAGCAUGAUGGAUUUUUCUUUGAAUUGUUCUCACUGUCAUUCUUUAAAUUUACCAUCAAAGGAUCAAAACAUCCAAAUUACAAAACUAAGUUUAUCAUUCAUGAGAAAAUGUGUUAAAUACGUAUCUUUUGUAAAGUAGCGGCUGCUUCUAAUUAGAAACCGGUCCUAUAGACAUACCUUAUGUAUCAAAAAGCUUUUUAAAUAUACUUACUGCUUUACUGUUACUUUCAUUUAAAAUAGGAUGAUUCAGUUUCUGAACUAGCCCUGUCUGUUCUCCAAAGGAACUAGGAUGAAUUUUGAGGAGGGGCUCUUAAACUUUGAGCAGAUCUGUAACUUCAUUGAGAGCAGACAUUUUUAAAAAUUCAUCACUGACAUUUAUUCAACAAAAAGAAGAUCAGAUUUUGCUAAAGCCUUUUGGUUGUGUCUCUUUUAGAAAUAACGUGUUGAUUUAGUUGCAUAUAGUUCAGCUCUUAAGGACCAGUCUUUAAGGCUUUAGCCAGAAUUUGUCUCCUAAAGCUGACUUUAAAAUGGCUUCCAAAAGGAUUUGCUGAGUUUCAGAACUGAGUAGGCUGCUAAUGAUUCAGUAGGCCCCCUCAUUUUCCUCCUACUCCUUAAAUUGAAGGCUCCUUCAUACCAUCUAGGUACCCUGAGUCAUCAUGGAUAAACUCUAAAGAAGAAUUGUCAUAUGGAAAAACUCUACAUGAAGUAAGAAUGUCAGAAAGCAGUCUGAGUCAGAGAUCAUUCAUUGCUCACAAUGAUAAAAUCUAUAGGUUGUGGGCUUCAUUUUAAAUCUUUUAACAUACUUCCAUGUAUGUCCUUAUUAUAGGAUUAUAAAUCCUAUAAUGCCCAUAAAACCAUCUGAGGUGUUUAUUCCCAGUUAAUUUCUAAUUGGUUUGGUUUUUAUUAUCUAUUACAUGAAAAGGAUUUUGUAUUUUUUAUUGAAUAAAUAGAGAGGAGAGGCAAUAUGAUACAGGAUAAAAACCACUAUAUCAGAAGUUAGGGGACCUGGAGUUCUGGUUUAUCUUCUCAAUAUGUGACCUUAUAUAUUUCAUUUAACCUCUUUGAGCUUGAGUUUCCUUAUCUUUACAAGGUCAGUAACUCCAUCACUCACACCCUCUUUGGAACCAACCCAUGGCAGAUACAGCUAGUAGCUGUAUCUGUAUCGGUAUCUGUAUCCCAAACCAGUUUCAGGUAACUUUUUUAUACAGCACUGUCAGAAACUAUAUAUAUAAUUGCCAUUCUGAUGAAAUCUCUUUGUCAUCUCAGCUAUAUUGGGUCUCUUCCAGCUCCAGGAUUCUAUGACUUUAAAUAAUUUGCCUAUAGAAAGUCUCUCUCUUCUAUCUAUACUGUCUCUUCACAUUGAGUGCUCAGGGUUGAAACUCACUGUAUGAGCUUAAGAAUUCUUUGUAGUCAGGGAUAGCAUGUUUAUGUUUCAUUUAGUGAUGUUAAAACAAAUGAUUGAAGAAAACUCAUGGGGGUACUUAAAAUUCCAAAUGAAAUGGUAACAAAUAACAAUGUUUAGUGCUAAUUUGAUGGAAACUCAUUUUAAGUUCUAAAUGUUUAUGGCACAGACCUCAGGUUAGUGAAAUUCGAAGUGAUGUAUUUGUCUGGAGGGCACAUGAUGAAGACAUAGGAAUUCUAGACCAAGAAAUAAAGAGGCCUGAGUUCUAGCUUUGCAAACUGUUUUUUUAACCUGGUUAGUGUCUUCAUCUAUUGUAAUGGUAUCAGACCAGUGUUUUUCAUUAAUGUAUUAUACAAAUUACCUAAGGAUCAUAUUAUAAUGCAUAUGCUAAUUCAGUAAGUAUGGCUGGGGCUUGAGAUUCUUCAUUUUUAGCAGGCUUCUGGGUGUGCUACUGCUAUAGGCCAUGGACCACACUUUACUUAUAAAAGUACUAUGCCAUUUCCAAGGCUCCUUCUGGUUUAAAGGGUCUUUAAACUAUAACUCCACUUCUUUUUCUCCAGCUCUUUCGUAUCACUAUUAAAUUUGUACUUUUUGAAACCACAUAUUCCUAGACUUAUUCCCUAUUUUCUCAGUCUGAGAGCUCCAUUAAUUUUGUUGUUUUUCCCUUUCCAGAAUGAACUUGACAUAGGUGGUCAUUCAAGUUAAAGCUAAGGUAGUAUAAUAGAGUCUUUAAUAAGAAGAAAACUUUAUUCAGAUGCCUCCCCCACUAAUUGGUAGCUCUUUUGCCUUGGACAGUUGACUCAGUUUACUUAAUCUCAAGGUUCUGAGAACAAGCCUCACCGGGACUUAUUAAAUCCCUUAUCCAAAAUGCUUGGGGCAAAAGGUGUUUUGGAUUUCAGAUUUUUUCAGAUCGUGGAAUAUUUGCAUUAUACUUGGAAGAGCAUUUCCUUUGAGAGUUGUGUUAGCACUUGAAAAGUUUCAGGUGUUGUAGCAUUUUGGAUUUCAGAUUUUCAGAUUAGGAAUGCUCAACCUGUAUCUUCCUGGUAAGGUUGUUGAAAGGAAUAGAGAUAAUAUAUAAAGUUCUCAGCACGAUGUCAAGCAUAAAGUAGGUACUCAAGAAUUGGAAGCUAUUUUUAUUAUUUCUACUGGCAUCCUGACUUGGUCUAGUGGAAAGAGAAAAAGGAGGGGGAAAGAUCUGUUGCCAAUUCAGUACCUUUCUCUGUGAGCCAAUUUAAAUUUUCAACUGCUUAUUAGACAUAUUAACUAAAAUUCUUCAAACUUACCAUAGUGAAAAAGACCUCUGUUUUCUUUCCAUAUCUGUUCUGCCUCCUACAAUACUGGUAGAGAUUACUGUUUCUGGCUGGGUGCAGUGGCUCAUGCCUGUAACCCCAGCACUUUGGGAGGCCAAGGUGGGUGGAUCAUUUGAGGUCAGGAGUUCGAGACCAGCCUGGCCAACAUGGUGAAACCCCAUCUCUACUAAAAAUACAAACAUUAAUUGGGCGUGGUGGUGUGUGCCUGUAAUCUGAGCUACUCCUGAGGCCGAGGCAGGAGAAUUGCUUGAACCUGGGAGGUGGAGGUUGCAGUGAGCCAAGAUGGCACCACUGCACUCUAGCCUGGGCAAUGGAGUGAGACUCCGUCUCAAUUUAAAAAAAAAAAAAAGAGAGAGAUUACUAUUUCACUCUCUACAUGCCGGUUAGGAUCCUGUCGUUUCUGCCUUUGUUUCUCGAGUACAGUUGGCCUUCUGUAUCCAUGGAAUCUGCAUCUGAGGAUUGAACCAAGCAUGGAUCAAAAAUAUUUGGAAAACAAAUAUAAUAAAAAAUAACAAUACAACAAUAAAUACAACUAAAAAGUACAGUAUAACAACUAUUUUCAUAGCACUUACAUUUUAUUAGGUAUUAUAAGUCAGAGGUCCCUACCCCCAGGGCAUUGACCUGAACCUAUGUGUGUAUAUAUAUAUGUGUGUAUAUAUAUAUAUGAAUUGCUAGAACUUUUUGACCCCUGAGAGCUUUAAGAAUAUAUCAAAAUUUAAAAUUUGGCACUACUUUAACAAAUUUAAUAUAAUAUCUUAUUAUUAAUUUUCCUAUUAGCUUUAGUAAUGAAAUUUGUUGAUAGCUAGUUUUUUAAUGUCUUAAGCAAACUGUGCUUUUGGACCAAGAAAUUCAUAAAGAACCAUGAAAACGAAGGUUCUCUCCUAGGUACUCAGGGCCUCAGGGAGAGAUAGGAGUAAAGGGUUAUGAAGGGCAGUAACAACAGAGUCUUUAUGUGUUGAUUUCUAGAACUGAUUUUAGUCUGAAAAUGAAAACCCAGUUCUUACCAAAAAGGAAAAUAAGUUACCCAUUGUGUUUUACUCUUCCUUUUUAACACCCAAAGUAUGAAAUGAAAUAAAAAAUAAUACAUUAUGGCUUCUAAUAUCAUUUAGAUAGAUUCUUCUAUUUCCUGUGUUAUAUUACUGUGUAUAUGAAUGAGCACAUCUGUUCCCAAAAGGCUUUAACAUUCUAUAGUCUCUAGGAAAUUUUAUUUUUUUCUUCAAAAUUUCUUGAAUAAAUUUUAUAGAAAUAUGUAUGCUUUUUUAUGCACCAAAUUAAAAUGAAGAUUUCGUAAGAUCUAAUUUAGCAAACUUUUUAAUGUCUUUCCCUUAUUUCUUCAAUAUUAAGUGCUGCAAAAUGAGCAAGACAGUUUCUCCCUUGGAGGAGUGUUCAGCUUUAAUAGAAGAUAGCACAGGGUCAUAUGUAACUAUAAUAUAAAACUGGAUAAGGCCCAUAAAAGAAUUGCAGAUAAACUAUGGGAGCUCAAAAAAGAUUAUACCCAGUUUAGGGAAUAAGGAAAAACUUUCAGACUGGGAAAAGAACAUCAAAUGGGCCUUGAAAUACUAUUAGAAUUUUUUACAAGUGAAUAGUGAUAACGUUAACAACACUUGUUUGCUGAGUAUUUAUUACAUAUUCAGUUUCAUUUUUUUCAAAAAUGUCUGAUAUAUGAACGUAGCAUAGUGGCAUAUGCCUGUAGUCCCAGCUACUCGAGUGGCUAAAAUGGGAGUAACCCAGGAGUUUCAGACUAGCCCGGGCAAUACAGCCAGACCUUAUCUCAAAAGAAAUUCUUUUUUUGAUAUAUGUGAUAUAGAGAGUAACAACCAUGUCACUUUAAAUUGGGGGGAAAAGUUGGGAAGAAUCUGGAAUUAUGGUGGAUUCAAAAGACACAUGAUUCAAAAUCUCAAAAUCAAAAGUCACAUAGCUUAUUGGGACACAUCAAAUGAGAAGCUUUCUACUGCAGCCACCACAAUAAUUUUUCGUAGUAUAUACUAGAGUUGAAAAUCAUUUCUAACAAAAAUUACAUUGUGUCUCUGGAGAGGUAAUCAGUGAUUUGCAUGAAAACUUAAUAGUACAUACAUUGCCUUAAAAAGUGCUACUUUAAUCUUCUAUCAUUUAAGAAAUUCCUGUGACUUUAUGUGGAUCAUCAAUACAAGCAAUUGUAGACUAUAUUCUAUUAUACAUAUUCUAGAAUCAGCAAUGUAUUUAUUUGUUUGGUGUUUACGUAAGUCUUAGUGUGUUUUAUAAAUAAUAGGAGGGUUUGUUUAAAGUGGGCUUUUGAAGAUACAGUGUGACUUUAAAAGAAUGGUCUUAGAAAACUUAUAAAUAGCCUAAAUAUGUACUGAAGAACAUUUCAUAAUCACAAAAAAAGAAAUAAUAUAUCUCAUGAAUUAUUAAGAAUUUGUUUUUUAAAUAAAGUCCUCUUUUUGAAAAGGUAUUAAGAAGAGGAAUUAGACAAAACUUGUUUGAAUAUGGUUGUAAUUGCAGUUUACUGAGUUAUAUAUAAAAAAGCCCAAUUAGUUUAAACAAAUACAGUAUCUGGGUUUAUGGUAUUCUGAGCCUCGUAUUUUUUCAUUGAAUGUCAGGGGUAUAUUAAAAUGCCUCCCUUUAUGUUUCUAUACAAAAGAUUGUUCUGACAGUAAGUUUAAGUGAUUUUCACAACUUAUUGCUGUCUAAAAAUUUCCCUUGACUUCACAUUUUGUUCUGAAUAUGUUGGUUUCUUUCCUCCACCCACACAAUGUUGAAGGCAAGGGAAGCAAGAGUUGCAAAGUAAUACAGUGAAUUUGAGAACCCUGGCUUUUUUUCAAAACAAAAUAAACCUUUAUUAUAAGAUUGCUUUUUAUUGAUACCAAAAAAGGGUGGCACUUUGGCAAAUGGUCAGUAAGUGUAUGAAUAGCCUAAUUGAUUUAGCUGGAAUGAAUAAGAAGCUUUGCUAUUUGUCCUUGUAGAUAGUUGGCUCAGUAAACAUUGUGAUGGUGAUAGACCAAAUUUUCCAUGGUGAAAGGUAAAACAGAACAGCAACAAAAAACUCAUCAAACUUAUAGAUCCAAAUAUCAGCAAUUUUGUGUCUGUGUCAAGGUCUUCAAAGAAGGAGCAAUGUGUUAAUUAGGAUCUCAUUUGAAUUUCUAUAGUGAAAAAAUAAUCAUUUUAACUUACAUAAAACCCAAGAGUUUGACAAAUGUUACUAUGUGAAAAUAUUAAUAGAGGAGAUCCUUGCUGAGAAUUUAAAUCUGCAUGAAAUUCAUAGAUGUGUGUAGAAAUUUAAAUUUAUCAUACACUCCGCAGUAAAUGCCAAUAAAGGUGGAUGGCAUAAUUAGGACAAAGAUAACAGUAGAAGCAAAAUAAGAAUUUUUUAAAAACCUUAUGGAUGUCACAUUAGUCUGACUCAGUCUGUAACUCUAGUUAGAAAUGUAAAAUUUUAGGGAUUUUUGGGCUACUGUAAGAAAAGAAUCUGCUUUGGGGGUGGGAUGUGAGGAGAAAGAAAUGUUUGUGGCAAUUAAGAUGUAUAUAGUAUAUUUAAGAAGUACAUUUGCAAUUCUAAUCACUUAGUUCAAAAGGAGAAAAAUAUAUCAUGUGUAACUUUAUUUACUUUUAAUACUAUUAUUAUUAUUACAUGAUUGAAAAUAGAAAAUCUUGAAAAAUUCUAGAGGGUAAAAGUGUUAUUUCUAAUUCCAUUAGCUCCUUUUAAGAUAGGAACAUUUCAUAUUAGUCUCCUAGCACAGAAUCUGAACCAUAAUAGGCACUCCAUAAAUGUUUACUGAACUAACCUGAAUUUUAGAAAUAUCAGGGUGCAAAGCAGAAUUAUUUUUCUAGGCUUUAAAACUAUACCACUGCUCCUUACCCCUGUACACACCUUCGAAUCUCAGUUUUGAUACAAAUAGGUUCUCAGUUUUGGGUGUGAAGAAAACUGGUUGAUAUUUUUUUUUAAUCUACUAAAUGUUGGCCAGAGCUGAAAUUGCCUGAAAGGGAACUUGAUUUAGCAGAAUUCCUUCUUUUCAGAAAGAAGGACUUAGACUAAAUUAUAUGAACGGGAGGAGCCUGUUUUUAUCUGAGAUGGUUGAUUGGAAAAAGAAUAGAUAAACUAAGGUGGAGAGUUGAUUUGAAAAAAGGAAAAAAGAUAGUCCUGUCUAGUGGUCAGUCCUAACAGUGUGGUUAAAGGGGAGCUAAAUUUCAACUUUCAGGGGUCAGCUGAGACAACCACCUAGAUUUUCCAAGUUAGUUCCAAUUUCAAGUACAAUAAUCCUUUGACAACAUAGAAAAGAAUUAUAGUUAGCAAAAUUGCAAUUGUCACAGUCAAGGUCUUGUUGGUAAUAGAGGGUUGGGGAAAAAGUUAAAACAGCAUUAAAUGAAUAUAUUUUUAACAUAACAAAAGUUCCCAGAAGACAUCCACUUCAAAUUCAAGCCAUAUUCAUCAAUGUUAAAAACCUUACUCUUCUCCCUGAUAGUGUGAGGAAAAAUAAAAUAAACUUAAAAUAAAAAACAAGAAAACCUCACUCAACAUUGUUUGAAAAACAUAACUGUGAUGUUAUGAUCUACUAAAGCAUGGUAUCCCAACAAAUUUCAUACAGAAUCAUGCCUGUCUGAAACUUUACAUUUUUUGUAGAGACAAGGACUCACUCUGUUGCCCAGGCUGGCCUCAAACUCCUGUGCUCAAGCAGUCCUCCUGCCUGGGCCUCCCAAAGUUCUGGGAUUACAGGUGUGAGCCACCUUGCUCGGCCUCAAAUAAACUCUUAAUGGCUUGGAAUUUAACAGGUCUUGUGCUUUCAUUCUCCUUUAUUUUGUUGUUGUUGUUUAAUAAAUAUCAGCACAAGUGUUAUUUAACAACCUGGACUUUUACAAAUUAAUAGGCGUUAAGGGAAUCUUUUCUUUGGUCUUGGUAGUCUAUCCAUCUUUCUAAGAGUAUAAAGAGAUUUUUCUUUACUAUACAGAUGUAAAGAGGAGUUAAUAAUUGUCAUACUUUUUGUUUUUUGAUUCAGCACUUCCUAACAGUCACUGAGCUUACAAAGCCAUGGUUCAUGAUUUCCACAAACUUACUUUUUAUUUAUCUCCUAACCAAACUCCAGGGAACCUACUGACUUACCCUUUCCUGAGAACACAAUAUACUUUUUACCCCUUGUCUUUUUUAUCUUUAUGCGAUUGUUUCUUCCACCUAAACUGGUUUUUUUUUUUCACUUAUCAAAGUCCGGUCUGUCUCUCAAGGUCCAAAUUGAAUACCUCUGCUAUGAAGCUUCCUCUUGUUCCUCUUCCUCCUAAGUAAUAACACUUUUCUUUGAAGUCUUACGGUAUUUAUGGUCUUUUGCAUUAAUAUGAUAUCUGUUCUAUACUGAUUUAAUUUACAUCCUUUUUUAGUAAACAUAAGUAAACAAAUGUUUGGUAUAGGGAGGCAUACCUUUUGCAUUAGUUUGAAUACUCCCAUAACUUCUGACCUUAUAGUGAAUGCUCAGUAAUAUUUGUUGGGUUAGUAAUUGUGUUGUUGGUGACUCUAGAUGCACUAAAUUAAAAGUAGGGAGACCCGCUGGGCACAGUGGCUCAUGCCUGUAAUCCCAGCACUUUGGGAGGCCAAGGCAGGCAGAUCACGAGGUCAAGAGAUCGUGACCGUCCUGGCCAACAUGAUGAAACCCCGUCUCUACUAAAAAUACAAAAAUUAGCUGGACAUGGUGGUGUGUGCCUGUAGUCCCAGCUACUUGGGAGGCUGAGGCAGGAGAAUCGGUUGAACCCGGGAGGCAGAGGUUGCAGUGAUCUGUGAUCGUGUGACUGCACUCCAGCCUGGCAACAGAGUGAGACUCCGUCUCAAAAAAAAAUAGGGAGACCACAGCCCUUGGUUUAAGAACUGCUCCAACAUCAAAGCAAAUUAAACUGCAAAGAAAGCUCACAAUGGUUAUUAAUAGAAGAAAUCAUUAAUUAGCAUUUUAUGGAGAGUAUAGGUUGAAUAUAUCCCUUAACCAGAUCCUUGGGACCGGAAGUGUUUUGGAUUUUGGAAUACUUGCAUAUAUAUUAUGAGAUAUCUUCGGGAUGGGACCCAUAAAAUUCAUUUAUGUUUCAUAUACACCUUAUACAAAUAGCUUGAAGACAAUUUUAUACAAUAUUUUUAUUAAUUUUGUGCAUGAAAGUUUGUGUUAAGUACUUACAUGUGGAAUUUUCCACUUACGAUGUCGUGUUGCUCAAAAAUUUCAGGUUUUGGAGCAUUUUGCGGAUUCAGAUUCGGGUUGUUCAACCUGUACUAAUCUAGGUACUUCUGUGGUGAAGGGAUAUCAUCAUCUGUUAACCUAGGUAUAUUAGUUAUUAGAAGAUUUUGACUUCUAGCUAUUUAACCAAAUAGAACUAUUAGCUAGCUAGAGGGACAGGCUAGGUAAUUAAUUAAAACAUUGGGUAUUUAUAUUAAAUACCAGGCAUUGGAUUAAAUACCAAAUCUGUUGGUUUGGUAAUGUCUUUGUCCUCAGAGGGAUCAAGUGAAACUUAUUGGUCAUGGGAUUAUAUUGAGCUAUGUAUUUGAAUAUUCAGCUUACUUCGAUGCUGUUGCUGUGGUGUAAUACAAAAAUCUAUUUGGUCUUUCUACCACGCUGUCUUCCUGGCACAGAGUUCCUAUAAUGCUGAGAAUUUUUUUGAGUGAUAGGAUGUCUUUUAUUAUUUAUAACAACCCCCUUUCUGAUCAUAAUAGGUAACUUAGGGUGGGGCCCUGAGAUGGCAUCAGGAUGGGGCUGGUCGCCAGAAGGACCAAGAAAUUAAGAGGGUUGGGACUUUUGUCUCACCCAGUGACCUCUGGGAAAGGGACAGAGGCCUGGAGAUUGAGUUUUUGGGUUGGUGAACACAUCAAGUUGCUGGGAGGGUGGCAUUCCUGGACAGGGCAUGGAAGCUCCACUGCUCUACCCUCCCCGCGCCCCCGCCCCCACCCCCACAUACCUUGCCCUGUGCAUCUCUUCCAUUUGGCUGUUCCUGGGUUGCAUUCUUUUUAAUAAACCAGUAAACAUAAAAGAAGUGUUUUCUUGUUCUUCUGUGAGCUGUACCAGUAAAUUAUGGAACCUGAGGAGGGGGUUGUGGGAACCCCCAAUUUAUAGCUAGUUGGUCAGAAGUCAGGUGGUUUGGGACUUUGAUUGGCAUCUGAACUUAGGGGAGUCUUGUGGCAUGAGCCCUUUAACUUGUGAGAUCUGACACUAAAGGUAGAUAAUAGUGUCAGAACUGAAUUGAUUUGUUGGAUGCCCAGUUGGUGUCAGAAUUGGAGAGUUGGUGGUUGAUGUCAGAGAGAACACUCAUUGAACAUGAUGCAAGAUUAUCAGCAAAAACAUAAACAAAAAAGCACAUGUUUAUGAUUAAAGCUAGUCUGAAACAGAUUAUGAGAUUUAAAAUUCCAAACCUAAGUGUCAAUUUCAUAAUUUCUGGUACAAAAAGCACUUCAUUUGGGAAAGCUUUCAGUUUUGCUUGUGAAAAUUUAUCUUGUAGAAUGUUCAAAUGAUUAGUUUCCCUCAGUUUCUCUGGCCAAGAAGUAGGAGUUAACAGUAUCUAGAAUUUUUAAAAUUUAUGUAGGUUAUAAAGUUGCAUAAGAUCGGUAAUAUAUUUGAAUUCCAGAGGUAUGUGCCAGCUUCCAGUGAACCUUGAGUCUAUAGCAGGCUUUUGUUUUUAAUGUGCUAGAGCUUUAUUUGCUUGCUUGCUUGCUUCGCUUUAUUGAGGUAUAAUUUUUAUACCAUUUAUGUAAACACUUAAAGUGUACACUUCAGUGGUUUUUAGUAUAGUCUCAGAGCUGUGCAGCACAAUCAAUUUUAGAACAUUUUCACCCGAAAAACAAAUCUCAUGUCAUAGCCUUUAGCUAUCAUUCCCCAAUUUCCUAUUUUCUCCCCUUUCUUUCCCCUCCCAGGCAACCACUAAUCUACUUUCUUUCUGUCUCUGGAUUUGCCUUUUCUGGACAUUUCAUAUAAAUGGAAUCAUACAAUAUGUGAUCCUUUGUGACUGACUUCUUUCACUUAGCAGAAUGUUUUCCAGGUUCAUCCAUGUUGUGGUAUAUAUCAGUAAUUCAUUCCUUUUUAUUGCAAAAUAAUAUUCCAUUAUAUGGAUAUACCACAUUUUGUUUAUCCGACUGUUGAUGGACAUUUGGGUUGUUUCUACUUUGGGGCUAUUAUGAAUAUUGCUGCUGUGAACAUUAAUGCACAGUCUGUGUGUGGACAUAGGUCUUCAUUUCUCCUGGGUAUAUACCUAGGAAUUGAAUUCCUGAGUCACAUGAGAACUUAAUGUUUAAUCUGGAGGAACUGCCAGAGUGUUUUCCAAAGUAACUACACCAUUUUACUUUCCCACUAGCCAUGAUUGAGGACUCCAGCUUUUCCACAUCCUUACCAAUAUUUGUCAUUAUCUGACUUUUUGAUAAUAGCCAUGGGUUUGAAGUGGUCAUUGUGGGUUUGAUUUGUAUUUCCCUAAUGGCUAAUGAGCAUCUUUUUAUGUACAUAUUGGCUAUUUGUAUAUCUUCUUUGGAGAAAUAAAUGGAUCUUUUACCAAAUUUUAAUUUCAUUUAUAUUUUAUUGAGUUAUGAGACCUUUUUAGGUAUUCUAGAUAUAAGUCCUUUAUCAGAUACAUGAUUUGCAAAUAAUUUUUCCCAUUAUGUGGGUUACCUAUGGCAGUACUUUUGAUACCUAGCUUUCUUUUGUUCGUUUAAAGAGACUGCCAGGUAAACACAGCCCACAAAGUGGGAGUAUGAACAGCCAAUUUAGGAAGGCAGUGCUCUAUCUGGUGAGCAAAAAGAAACAAAUCUCCAUGGUAUGCCUUUCAUUAAAUUUUUGUCUGAUUUUCAGCUUUUUCUUUGUGGUAUAAAAUUAUAACAACAUAUAGAAAAGAGUGGAGCUAAAGUUGAACACUUGGCCAUCUCCUGUAAUAAUACACAGUACAAGGUAGGAGUUACUUAUUGGCUGACUGCUCUGUUCUUUAGUGCUUGUGGUAUUGCCUCCAAAAUUAAUGAAACAGACGCCAACAUAGGAGUCCCAAGAUCAGUUAGCAAGCUGCACUACUUAGCCCUAUGACUGUCAUCAAAUAACUUACCCUCUCUGAAUAUAGAUUUUUCUCAUCUAUUAUAAAAUGAAAUUGGAAGGAAAAUUGAACAAAUUGCACAGUAUAUUCUUUAAGGUUCUUUCCAGCUUUAAAAUGUAAUUAUAUAAUACAGUAAUACAGUGAUUAUUUUUCUUCUUAAACCUUGUUGAAAAAUCUUAGGCCUAAUGUACAUUUUCUCAAAAGGAUUGGAGUUAGAUGGAUUUGACAAGUAAAAAACUGGGCAUGUUUCGAUAUUCAAUACAAAUGUACUGUAGAAUAGCAAAUGCCAUCUGCGUGAAUUUGCAUUGUGGGAUGGAGGAACGUGACCUAAGAGUCACCAGUGGAGUGGAACUAAAGGAAGAAAUAAUUUAUGCACCUGCUGAGGGUGUGGCUAGAGGUAAAGGGACUGUGACGAAUGAGUCCUUGAUUGCCUUCUUGGAAGUAUUCAGAGAUCAUUAAAGAAGCAGGACGUUCUCAGAGGUCAGUGUGUCCAAGGGUGAAACAAAAACCUAAUAAGAAAAAUAGGUCCGUAAGAAAAGAGACAUCUGAAAAGGCCUAGAAAUUGUGAGGAAAUAAUGCAAAAGGUGUCCCAAGGCUCCUGACCAGUGAACAAAGAUUUGAGAAAGACAGCCAAGCUCAUGUUUUCUCCUGAUCAAGAAAAUCAUCCAUCUAAAGCACCAGUAAAAUAUGGUGAACUCAUUGUCUUAGGGUAUAAUGGGUCUCUCCCAAAUGGCGAUAGAGGAAGGAGGAAAAGUAGGUUUGCUUUGUUUAAAAGACCUAAGGCAAAUGGGGUGAAGCCCAGCACUGUGCAUAUUGCUUGUACUCCUCAGGCUGCAAAGGCAAUAAGCAACAAAGACCAGCAUAGCAUAUCAUAUACUUUAUCUCGGGCCCAGACUGUGGUGGUUGAAUAUACUCAUGACAGCAACACCGAUAUGUUUCAGAUUGGCCGGUCGACUGAAAGCCCCAUUGAUUUUGUAGUAACUGACACGGUUCCUGGAAGUCAAAGUAAUUCUGAUACACAGUCAGUACAAAGCACUAUAUCAAGAUUUGCCUGCAGAAUCAUAUGUGAACGGAAUCCUCCCUUUACAGCACGGAUUUAUGCUGCAGGAUUUGACUCAUCAAAAAACAUCUUUCUUGGGGAGAAGGCUGCCAAAUGGAAGACAUCAGAUGGACAGAUGGAUGGCUUGACCACUAAUGGUGUUCUUGUGAUGCAUCCACGCAAUGGGUUCACAGAAGACUCCAAGCCUGGAAUAUGGAGAGAAAUAUCGGUGUGUGGAAAUGUAUUUAGCCUACGUGAAACCAGAUCGGCUCAGCAGAGAGGAAAAAUGGUGGAAAUUGAAACCAAUCAGUUACAAGAUGGCUCGUUAAUUGACCUCUGUGGUGCAACAUUGUUAUGGCGUACUGCAGAAGGCCUUUCCCACACUCCUACCGUGAAGCAUUUAGAAGCUUUAAGACAGGAAAUCAAUGCAGCACGACCUCAGUGCCCUGUAGGGUUCAACACACUAGCAUUUCCUAGUAUGAAGAGGAAAGACGUUGUAGAUGAAAAACAACCAUGGGUAUAUCUAAACUGCGGCCAUGUACAUGGCUAUCAUAACUGGGGAAACAAAGAAGAACGUGAUGGAAAAGAUCGUGAAUGUCCUAUGUGUAGGUCUGUUGGUCCCUAUGUUCCUCUGUGGCUUGGAUGUGAAGCUGGAUUUUAUGUGGACGCCGGCCCUCCAACCCAUGCGUUUAGCCCGUGUGGGCAUGUGUGUUCAGAAAAGACAACUGCCUAUUGGUCCCAGAUCCCACUUCCUCAUGGUACUCAUACUUUUCAUGCAGCCUGUCCCUUUUGUGCACAUCAGUUGGCUGGUGAACAAGGCUACAUCAGACUUAUUUUUCAAGGACCUCUAGACUAACAGACCAUUGUCUUGCAGGACUACAUUAUAAAUUUAUAAGCUAAGUGAGUUGGGUUUUCGAACCUGUUGUCCACGUCACAGUUUUUCUGCUCUGGUCAUUUGCAUUAAGAUGAAGAAUUUUUUAAAACAUUUAUAAUAAAUAGUAGCAAUUUCUGAGCAAAAAUCUGGGAAACUCAAGCAAAGGAAUUUCUGAAAGUAUCAGUCUUCUGAAUUCUGAGUUUUGAAAAUAUAUUUUGAGGAGAAAAAGACAUAGUCUAAUUUGAUGCCUUCCUUUUAGUGUUUUUGAAUCACCUAUCCUCAGUGCUGAAAUUGUUUUGUAUAACUGAGGGUACUGUUGGUUCAAACUAUGUUAGUUUACAGUUUGUUGCAAACAUUGUAAAAUACAGCGACAUGUAUAUUAACUUUUUUCUAUUUAUCUUUAUUAUAGAAAAUACCUUAGAAUGUUCUUGAUAGAGUAGCAUGGUAACGAUGGUGUCACACCCUUGGUGUGAAUGGUAGCUUAGUGAGCAACCUAGCUCAAGGAUUUGCAAAGUUAGGAAGAAGGACGAGAGAGCCUCUCUCCCCACCCCAAUCUAAAUAUGGAAUUUGGUAAAUUAGAAUACUUUGUAAUUUGUAAGACCAAAUUCAUACUAAUUACCCGCGUGAAAGGUGUUUGUUUUUAACAACAUUGAAGAUAAUCAGGAAAGAUUUUUUCUUAAUGUUUCUCUCGAGCGUAGUACUAUAACAAAAACUUAAUGCUAAGAAACAUUUUAUAUGCUCCUUUGGAUAUGCAAUUUAAUCUAGAUUAUCUAUUUUUCUCCCAUGAUAACUAAUCUGUUUUUAGUAUCAGCAGCAUUUGGCAAGUUUAUUUUUUGGAUAUAAACUGUGGUUCAUCUGUUCACUGUUUCUAGAAAAAAAUCAUUGCCAUAAGAAAAAGUAUAAAUUAGCAAGAAAGGAGAGUGACUUGAUUUGCUUUUGGAAAAAGAAAUGCUUAAUUAAUUAUUCUGUAUUUGGCCUUAUUCGGGCAUUAGGAAAUCUAGAGAUCUAAAGGGUUGAAUGACAAUAGUGCCCCCGUUUUUAGCAGACCAGCCUUAACUCUGGGUUUGAAUCCUAAGGAGAUUGCCACAGUGAGACUUAAGGAAAUGUUUGGUUGGCAGAUGAGCACCAAUGACUGCAGCGUGGAGUGACGCACUGCAUGGUCUGUUUAUUCUCUAAUUCCAAUAUGUCUUUUGCUUCCAGAAGCAAGAAAAGUUUCUUCUCUCCCCUCCUUCCCACCCUUUUUUCAAAGGCACCACAAGUAUAGACAGUUGCACUACAUCAAAUCUUUUUUUGACACUUGUAGAAACCAGUACACUUUUAGAUUAGACAGUAUCUUCUUUUAAUAUUUUGAUUUGUUUUCCUUUAGUUUGAAAAGUUGUAUAAUACUUAACUGACUGUAGCAAAGUUUUAUAUGUGGUAGCAUACCUUUAAUUUAUCCUAUUACAAAACUGUUCUGAAUUUUCUUUUGGUUUUUAAAAAACAAAACUUGUUGCUUAGAAGCCAUGAAUUAUUUUAUUUUACUUCAACUGUCGAAACUUCCUUGUUUUAAAAAAUGAUCAUUUGGGUUCACUCAGGAAAUGCAUGUCAGGAAACUUGUAUUAUAAGUUUAUUAGUUGUGAUGUAUCAGUAACUGCUGUUACCCCUUUUUCAAAGAAAUGUAAUUGAUUUUGAAGUUUUCUAGAUUGUCACAUGCUUUGUGACUAAUGCAAGAAAGCAAGUCCUGUGUUGUAUUUGUUCUAGUCAUUUUUAUUCAGGCUAUAUAUUGUAGCUUAAUUUUUAUUUGCAAUUAAUUUAUUUAAACUAAGUAAAUACUUUUCAAAAUACAUAAUUGAAUUCGUCUCUGUGAGUUCAUUUUUGCAUAAUCGAGAAUGAGAAACCAGAAGUGAAAACUGUGAACAACUCUAUUCCACACUCCAAAAAUACUCAUUUGAAAUAGAUGAAGAGUUUGCAUUUAAUGUAACACUUUAAAGUAUCUGGUUCUUUUUUAAAAGCAUCUCUUACUAAUAAAGGAACUUUGUUAGUGGUUGAAUAA